AGUGACUGGUGAGCGGCUCCUAGGUCUGCUCCUGCCUCCAGUAGAAGCAGCCACAGGAGUCCUGGCCACAGCCCCCAUUGCGGCCCCCAUCGUGCUGGGUGCUGGCUUUUGGAAAUCCCUGCAUACCCGCAACGGCUCCCGUGGUGGGGGUGGAGGUGGAGGAGCUGGUCAGGCCACCCAGAGGCAUCUUCCUCAGUGGAGCCUUCUGCCAGGUACCUCUCAGCUGUUUUCCAAAUGACUACUUAGCAUUUCCCUGCCUCGAUCCCCACAGCAGCCCUGUAGGGAAGGAGUGGCCCAUUUCACAGAUGAGAAACUCGAGGCUUACAGAGUCAGUCUGCGCAACUGGGGCUGGGGGCAAUGUGCUGGUUAAAAUGCAGAUUCCCAUCUCCCCCCGCCCCGGAGGAUGGGAUGUGGGAAUCAGGGUCCAGGCCUUGGUGUUCUAAGCAGCCUCUCCAAGGAGCUGCGUUGUCAGGAGAGUGGGAAGCAGAAGCAGGAGCCUUGGGCCUUACAGUUCUGGGAGUGUGCUCUGGCCCUGCUGUUUGCUCAGUUGGGGCAAUUGCAUCAGCUUCCUGGGCUUCCUUCAGCUUUCUCAGCUGUGAGCUGGAGAGAGUGGUGCCCACCUCCAAGGGGCCUGGUGAAAAUUCCAUGAUCAGUUCGUUUAUCUCACUUGGGAUAGUGGAAUUCCUGGAGAGUUCAAUAAAAUGGUUUGUUGCUAUUGUUCCACAUGGGAUUUACUACAAAAGCAAUUUCAGAAACAUCCAAAAAGAUAUCCAUGUGCAUAAUUGACAGUAGUGUAUCUGCUCAUCUCCUUCGAAGUGGGAGUUUCACAGGAUGGUGAAUCAGGGUUGCUCUACCCCCAUUUUAGAGAUUAAACUACAGCAGGCAGGGCAAGGUGGCUCACGCCUAUAAUCCCAGCACUUUGGGAGACCAAGACAGGAGGAUCACCUGAGUCCAGGAGUUCGAGACCAGCCUGGGCAACAUAGUGAGACUCCAUCUCUACAAAAAAAAAAAAAAAUUAGCUGGGCAUGGUGGCCUGCACCUGUGGUCUCAGCUACUCAGGAGGCUGAGGCGGGAGGAUCACUUGAGCCCGGGAGGUUGAGGCUGCAGUGAGCUGUGUUCACGCCACUUCCACUUCAGCCUGGACAACAGAGUGAGACUGUCUCAAACAACAAAAAAAGAAACUACAGCAGACCCUUGAAUAAUGUUUUGUUAUAAAACAUUGAUGAGAAAAAAAAGUAUUUCCUGGCUGGGGCCACUGUCUGUUGGGUUUGCACGUUCUACCCACGUCUGCGUGGCUCUUCUGCAGGCACCCCCACCCACCUACCCACAUCCCAAACCUGUGCCUGUCAGGUUCAUCAGCACGUCCGCAUGGUCCCGGUGUGGGUGAGUGUGGGUGUGUGGGCGUGUGUGCCCUGCGAUGGGAGGGCGUGCUGGCCAGGGCCGGUUCCCGCCUUGUUCCCUGAGCAGCUGGGAUGGGCUCUGGCCACCCGUGACUUGGAACUGGAAUAAGUUUGACAUCUACAGGAAGGUGCCCAAGGACCUUACGCAGCCAACGUACACCGGGGCCAUUAUCUCCAUCUGCUGCUGCCUCUUCAUCCUCUUCCUCUUCCUCUCGGAGCUCACCGGAUUUAUAACGACAGAAGUUGUGAACGAGCUCUAUGUCGAUGACCCAGACAAGGACAGCGGUGGCAAGAUCGACGUCAGUCUGAACAUCAGUUUACCCAAUCUGCACUGCGAGUUGGUUGGGCUUGACAUUCAGGAUGAGAUGGGCAGGCACGAAGUGGGCCACAUCGACAACUCCAUGAAGAUCCCGCUGAACAAUGGGGCAGGCUGCCGCUUCGAGGGGCAGUUCAGCAUCAACAAGAACCAGGAGCUUCAGAUCCUAAGUCAAGUGGGUGAACGCAGUGCCCUUGGGAGGGCCGAGGCACCCGGUGGCAGCUGGCAGGGUUUUGCUCAGCACGUGCCGGCCUUCCUCGAAGCUCGGUACUGUCACAGUGGAGCCUCUCAACAACGCUGUGAGGCAGCACCAUUUGACAGCCGUGAAGAGAAUGACGGGGUGCUGUGGUGGAGAAUGAAGGAGGAGACCCCUGAGGUUACAAAGGAAGCCCUGUCUGAAGACUGAAGAUGAAGAUGCACAGAUGAACAGACGUACACGCACACCUCCUCACUGUGGGCCCCCCGCCCCCGGGGAGAUGCAACCACCUGGGCUGAAAAAAUAUAUGUACCCCAGAUGGUGACCAAGAAGGGAUCGUGCUUAUUCAAGCACCUGGAGUGACAACCCACGAGACAGCCCUGCCACCAAGCCCUCCCACCUCUUGGCAAACACGCCCAAGACUGCAGUCUGCUCCCCUUAGAAUGGGCUGUGCUGGAGCCCCCAGCCAGCUCUGGGUGAACUUGUCCUUUGGGGUCAGACAGACCUGUGGUCAAGGAUCCCGGCUACCAUGGUCACUGGUUGAAUGACUCUGGGCAGUUUAGCUUCUCUGAGCCUCAGGUUCCUCAUCUGUAGAAUGGGGAUAAUAAUACCUCACAGGCUGUGAAACAUGAACAAACUCUGCAGUAGAGACUGGACAAGCAUCCUGGCCUGCCUCAUCUCCCGUCAGUGCAAAGUUUCCAUGACCUCAUCAGCUGGCACCCACCUUACAAGUGCGCCUGUGGAAGGCACAUGGAGGGCGUCCAAGAAAUGGGCCUUCUCUGGUCAGGGGAGUGCCAGGGAGUCUUUGAAAGGCUCACACCAGCCUUUCUUAGACCCGCGUUAUGGCUGCCACGUACUAGGUUCUUACCCAGCCCUUUCCACAUAUUAGCUCCUUUAGUCCUCACAGUAGCCUGGAGGAAACUGAGGCACAGGAGGUUAAGUGACCUGGUCAAGGUCACGCAGCCAGGAUUUUAACACAGGCAGCCUAGCACCAGGGCCCUGGCCCUCUGAGCUCACUGCCUGUGGCUGCUUCUCCCAACAUCUUGGUUACACAUGUCAUGACCAGCUGUGUCUGUGUGCCCCAGGUCACAGCCUAGGGCACCCUCUGCCCCAUACUCCUGGAGGGAGUAGAGACCGUCCCCCACCCCAGCCCAGCCACUUUCCCUUUGAGGAACCGCCCAUCAAGAGGUGCUCAAAGAAGCCACCAGGGUCCAUGUGCUGUGAUGGCAAGGUCAGCAGCCAGCCCCCGCACCUCUCUCCCAGCAUCAGGCUGAGACUUGUCCCAUGGCCUCCUUAUCCGACCCCCAGGAAGUUGACCAGCAGCCAGAUGUCAGAGUUUGCGUGUUUUGAGCAGCAGCGGCAGCCUCACCAGAGACCCCACGGUGACCUCGUUUCAUCAGCCAGCCCCGCAGGAGGAGGACAGGAUGGGGUGAGGGGUAUGGGGCCUGGCUCCAGCUAUAUGUUUUUAAAAUCCAUCAGAGACACUGACGUAGGUUCCUAAGUCACAGGCUCUAAAAGCGUUGCUGUUUCUUUCUUCAGCCCAGCAUGUGCUGGCAUGAGUCAGCCACCUGUGAUGGAUUUGGUGUGGAGGGGGAGUGGGUUCCUGAGUCACAGCCUCGCACGGCCCGGCAGGGGUGGCAGGUGCUGAGGGGACAGCCUUCUUGACUCACUUCACUCCCGGAGCACGCGGCCCAGGCCCCAAUCCCAGUUCUGAACUCUGCCAUGGCCCGAUCUGCGGAAGGCCCUGUGUCACUGCGUAGAAAACCUCUGGGAGGACACACGCCUUAUGGCUGUGGGUUUCUUACUCCCAGGGGUGGUCAGCAACAGGGUCUUUAGUCUGACUGUGUCUCAUGACUGUUUUAUCAUGAAAAUGUACCCAGGCAUUAUUUUUAUCGGUGAAAAUGAGGCAUAAAUGUUAAAACCCACAGUGGGCUUUUCCUCACGCCCUGCCUGUGAGUGUUCCCUCUUCCGGGAGGGCCCUUCUUGGUUGGCUCCGAUGACAAACAUGUUCACCCUACAAACCCGAUCUGAGGCCAGCUGCGGGCUGCUUUGUAUGCAUCACCUCAAUGAAUCCUCCCAGUAAUCUUCUGGCUUUACGCCCAUUUCGCUGAUGGAGAAACUGAGGCAUGGAGUGGUUACUGACCUCGCCUAAGGCUCCCCAGCUAGGAAGUGGGGCUGGGCUUGGGGCCAAGUGUAGAACUCAGAGCAACCGCUCUACUAUGGGUUAUUGGGUCCCUGAAGCAGGCGAUGCUGUCCCUCGAGGGAGAUCUUGCCACGCCUUUGUUUCUGCUCCACUCCUGACCCAGCAAGUGUCCCUUCUCCACUGUAGCCUGCAGCUCGCUCCACUGCGAGUUUGCUGAGGCCGAGGCUACAGGCUGUCAGCUUGAUGCCUCCCCUGUCAGCCACAAGCUCGGGCCCUGCUGAAGUAGGAAUAUUCCUGCAGGAAGUCCCCAACUUUGUGUUUGAAACAGACAUGCUUACAAAAUCAGACUUUGAUGGGCUGCUGCACGAUAAGCUAUAUUCCCUCCUCGGACACAGCUCGCACAGUCUUCUUCAUUGGGCUGGAAUAAGGUAACCCCCGAGUUUUUCAGUGUGGCAUCUGGGGACCUUUGAUAAACAGCCCCAACUCCUCCCUUGUGCCUCUUUGUUUCCUGCUGCUGCCAGCACCGCCACCUCCGUCUCAUUUGGAGUUCAAUAAUACCAGACUCUUAGUUCCUUAGACAGCCCACAUGCUGGGAAGUUUCUGUCCUCUGCACCUGUUCAUGCUGUUCCCUCUGCCCAGAUGCCUUUCGCUCUCUUCCUGAGUAAUGCAGACUCAUCUUCAGAGCCUUAACACAGGAUGUCCUUCCCCCUGGGAAGCCCUCCCUGAAUACAGCCUGCACCCUCAAUUGAGCCGGGGGCCUUCCCUGUAACCCCCAUGGUCUGCAAAUUCCUCUGGGCCAGGGUGGAUCCCACAGAGUCUCAUUGUCUGUUCCAAGUCUGUGUCACAGGGGCUUGGCCAAGGCCAGAUUCUUGUCUGCUCAUCUCCCCAGUUCCGGCAUCUCCUGAAGGACUGGCGCCAUGUGGCCAUCAGCCCAGGCUGCGGAGGUAGAUGGCAUCCAGGCAUCAGAGGAGGGAGCAGUGCGUCCAACAGACGUGAGCUGAGACUGCAGCUCUCGACAUGUGACCUUAGCAAGUUUCUUCACUGCUCUGAGCCUCCAUUUUCUUUUCUGUAAAAUGGGAAUUAUCAGAUGACAAAGUCAAAGGA